ACUUCCGCCCCCGCGGCAAAGCAGGGAGGUCGGAGGACUGGAGAGGUGGGGACCCUGGGGAGGUGGCUGCUCGGAGUCUAGGUGACGGGGCGAGACGGGGCCGGUAGGUGGCGGGAGGGGCCGGGCCGGAGCCGGCGGGAGGGCCAGGCCCGGAGGCCCCCACCCUGGCGUGCCUGCCCCGGCCGCGGCUGAGGAGGAGGAGGAGGAGGAGGAGGAGGAGGAUGAUCUCCAGAUACACUCGGAAGGCGGUGCCACAGAGCUUGGAGCUGAAAGGAAUAACAAAACAUGCUCUUAACCAUCAUCCCCCUCCAGAGAAGCUGGAGGAAAUUUCCCCCACCAGUGACAGUCAUGAGAAAGACACAAGUUCCCAAAGCAAGUCUGACAUCACAAGAGAAUCAUCUUUUACAUCAGCCGACACUGGGAAUUCACUGUCUGCUUUUCCAAGUUAUACAGGCGCAGGGAUAUCUACUGAAGGAAGCUCGGACUUCUCCUGGGGAUAUGGUGAACUCGAUCAAAAUGCCACUGAAAAAGUCCAGACAAUGUUCACAGCCAUUGAUGAACUCUUGUAUGAGCAGAAGUUGAGUGUGCAUACCAAGAGUCUACAAGAAGAGUGCCAACAGUGGACAGCUAGCUUUCCUCACCUCAGGAUUCUAGGUAGGCAGAUAAUCACUCCAAGUGAAGGUUAUAGAUUGUAUCCUAGAUCCCCUUCUGCUGUUUCCGCUUCAUAUGAAACAACCUUGUCUCAAGAAAGAGAUUCUACUAUAUUUGGUAUAAGGGGAAAGAAGUUACAUUUUUCAUCUUCUUAUGCUCAUAAAGCAUCUUCCAUUGCCAAAUCCUCCAGCUUUUGUUCUAUGGAAAGAGAUGAGGAAGACUCUAUAAUCGUCUCAGAAGGAAUAAUUGAGGAAUACCUAGCAUUCGAUCACAUAGAUAUAGAAGAGGGAUUUCAUGGGAAGAAAUCAGAAGCAGCUACAGAGAAACAGAAAUUAGGGUAUCCUCCCAUUGCUCCAUUUUACUGCAUGAAAGAAGAUGUCCUUGCUUAUGUGUUUGACAGUGUAUGGUGCAAGGUUGUGAGCUGUAUGGAGCAGUUGACACGUAGUCACUGGGAAGGAUUUGCCUCUGCAUUAAACUAUCAAAAUGGUGCCAGCUAUGACCUUGUGACCACAGAGGAUGGGACCUCUCUUAGGGCUGGUGUCCUUGUAAGAAGAGGAAGGGACAGCGGAGAUCUCUUUCUAUUUACACGUGGAGAAAAGGCCAUGUGAGGACAGAGAAAGAAGGUGGCCACCGGAAAGCCAGGACAGCACCUUGAUCUUGGACUUCUGGCCUCCAGAACUGUGAGAAAAUAAAUGUCCAUUGUGUAAUCCACCCAAUCAGUGCUAUUUUGUUAUGGCAGCCCUAGCAGACUAGUACACCAUGCAAUGGAAUAUUAUUCAGCCACAAAGAGGAAUUAAGUACUGAUACAUGUUACAACAUGGAUGAACCUUGAAAAUAUGCUAAAUGAAAGAAGCCAAUCACAAAGCACCAUGUAUAUGGUAUGAUUCCAUUCAUAUGAAAUGUCCAGAAUAGGCAGAGCCAUAGAGACAGAGUUUAGUGGUUGCUGGGGGAUGGAUGAAGAGGGAAAUUGAGAGGUACCAUGUUUCUUUUCGGAGUGAUAGAAAUUUUUUGAAAUUACAUAGUGGUAAUGAUUGCACAACAUUGUGACUAUAUUAGAAACCACUGAACUGCAUACUUUAAAAUGGUUAAAAUGAUGAAUUUUAUGUUAUAUGAAUCUUAUUUUUAAAAAAAUUUUUAAAAUUCUUUCAGCCUGAAAAAUGUCCAUUAAUAUUUCUUGUAUGUGGGUCUGCUAGUGAUUAACUGUUUCUUUUGUAGAUAUGAAAAUUCCUUUAUUUUGCUUUCAUUUUUGCAAGAUAAUUUUAUGAACUAUGUGAAUAGUUUGCCUUCUAGUACUUUUAAAAUGCUGUCCAUUUCUUCUCGCUUGCAUUGUUUCUGAAAAGAAAUUUGUUGUCAUCCUUAUCUUUGUUCCUUGGUGCAUGUAUUUUUUUUUCCUGGCUGCUAAGAUUUUCUCUUUAUCACUGGUUUUGAACAAUUUGACUAUGAUGUGCCUUAAUGUAGUUUUCCCCAUGUUUCUUCUGCCUGGAGUUUGUUUAACUUCAUAGAUUUGUAGGUUUGUUUUCAUUGUUUGGAAAGCUUUCAGCCAUUAUUUCUUCAGAUUUUUUUUUCUGUCCCCCAUCAUCCGUCAGGACUUUGGUCACUCAUAAAUUAGUCCAUUUGAUCAUUGAUCCCUCAGGUAACUCAUGCUUUAAAAAAAUUUUUUUUGUAUUCUUUUUUUUCUGUGUGUAUUUCAUUCUGGGCAAUUGCUAUUGUUAUGCCAUCAGUGUUCAUUAUCUUUUCUUCUACAACGUUGAAUCUGCUCAUUUAGUGUAUUUCAUGUGAGAUAUUGUCAUUUUCAUCUCAAAGUAUGAUUUGAGAGAGACAUAUAUAUUUUCCAUGUCUCUAUUUGAUAUUUUGAAAAUGUGGAAUAAUUUGAAUAUCUGUGUUAAUUCUAGGUUGGUUUCAGUUGAUACUUCCUUCAUUAUGGCUUGUAUUUUCCUGCCUGGUGAUCUUUGAUUAGAUUUCAUACAUUGUGCAUUUUACCUUACUAAGGGAUGAAUUUCUUUUUAUUACUGCAUAUUUUCUUGAGCUUUGUUCUGAAAUGCAAUUAAGUUACUUGCAAACAGUUUGAUCCAUUCUGGUCUUUCUUUUAUGAUUUGUUAGGUCUGGAGCAAUGUUCAGUCUAGAGCUAAUUAUUACCCACCUAUGGAGGCAAGAUCUUAUUCUGCCCAGUGCUCCAUGAAUUGAGUUUUUCUGGUCUGGAGAGUGGGAACAGGCAGUAUUCCUUGUUCCACGUGAGCAGCAAGUACUGUUCCCUUCUUUCACUUUUUUUUUUCCUAGCCUCAGGUGGCUUCUUCUCAUAUGUGCACUGAUAGUACAUUUUGAAUGCUCAAAUGAUGCCCCACCCUCUGCAGAUAUCAUGGGUUCUCUUCCUAUUUCUCUUCUUUAAGAUACUCUGUUCUAUGAAUCCGAGCUGCCUUGGUCUCUGGACUCUCAACUCAGGGAGUCCACCAGGCUGUGCCUCAGUUCCCACUCUUUAUGCCAUAUCUUGGAAACUUUUUCAAGGCAAUUGCAGGUCCAGUCUCAUUUGUUUAUCAUCUCAGGGUUUACUGACUUUCAUUAUCUGAUAUACAGUGGUCUUGAAAGCCAUUGUUUCAUUGUUUUAGGAGAGUAAACCCAGUUCAUGUUACUCCAUCUUGGCUGGAAGCAGAAGUCCAACAUUUUUAAACUUUUUAUUGAAUCACAGCUUGCCAAGAGUAAAAGGGAAAAAAAAGUUUUUAUUGAAGUGUAAUAUACACAUAGAAAAUUACAAAGUAAAUUUACAUCAAGUAAGCUUGAGGAUUUUUUGUCUCUACAAAAAGUAAAAAUAAUUAGCCAGGGCGUGGUGGUGCAUGCCUGUAGUCCUAGCUACUCAGGGGACUAAAGCAGGAGGAUCCCUUAAUCCCAGGAGUUUGAGACUGCAGUGAGCUAUGACUGUGCUAAUAUACUUCAGCCUGGAUGACCGUGCAAGACCCUGUCUCUAAAAAGAAAAACAGUAUGCUUUUAUGACCAGCACCCAGAUCAAGAAUAUUGCCAGUACUCCAGAAGCCUUUCUCAUGCUUUCUUUCAGUCAGCUACUUAAUCCGUACCCCCACAAGAUAACCCCAUCCUGACUUCCAACAGCACAGAUUAAUUUUGCCUGUUUUAAAAUUUUGUAAGAAUGGAUUCAUAUAGUAUAUACCCUUAUGCAUCUGGCUUCUUUUAUUCAAUAUUAUAUUUGUUAAAUUCAGUUAUGUUUUGCUCGCAACAAGUUUAUUCCCAUUGCUUAUAGUGUUCCAUUGUAUGACUAUAUCACACCCUACUGUUGAUGGAUAUGUGGGUGGUUUGUCUAGAAUAUAAUACUAUUAUGAAUAUUUUUGUAUAUGUCUUUUGAUGAACUUAAGUACUAGACGCAUAAGGGUAGAAUUGCUAGGUCAGAGGAUAUGCUAUUCUAACUUCAGUGGAUAUGGCCAAAAAAAUUUUCAAAGUGGUUAUACCUACUUACAGCCUCUCCAGUAUUGUGUGAGAGUUCCAGUUGCUCCACAUUUGCCACACUUGAUGUGUGGUCUUUGUGGGUUUGUUUUAUUUUUAAGCCACUAUGUUGUAUGUGUGUUAGGUUUUUUUUUUUUUAAGCUUGUAUUAGAGAAUAGGACUAGCACUCUCUUUAAAAUGAACUAGUUUAUAUUAUAUGAGGUUAAUUUUUUUGAGACACAGGACAGGUGGUAAUUAAAAGUCCAGAGUCAUACCCAGACUCCCAUAAUAAUAAACCCUGGUAAUAAACAAAGGAACUCCUUCCAGUUUCAGUGUAUCAACCACCACGUACCAGAUAAAAUCUUAUUUCACCUUUCACAAUUUACCAGUGUUGGGCUGUGAAUUAAUAUUUUUAUUUUUCUGUGCAUUCAUAAAUUAAGAUUAUUUUAUUGUAUUGUAACUGUAAUUUUGAGACUAAAGUCUAAAAACAAGACAUCAUGAAAUGGAGCUGGAGGAUCUCUAAUUGGCAUUUAGUAGGUUGACUGAAAUACCUUAAAACAGGGGUCAGGAAACAACUGUCUAUGCAGAGGCUGGUGGUAAAGAUUUCAGUCUUUGACAACCAUCCAGUCUCUGUUGCAACUACUCAACUCUGCCCUUGUAGCAUGAAAGCAGCCAUAAAUAAGAUGUAAAUGAAUGAGCUUGGCUGUGUACACUAGUACAUACUCAGUACAUAUGUUCACCAAAAGAUAGGUGCAAGAAUGUUCAUAAAUAACUAGAAAACAUACAUCAGAAACUACCCACAUGUCCAUCAACAGUAGAAUGUGAUAUAUUCAUACAAUGGAAUACUAUACCACUAUGAGAAUAAACAAAUGAUUAUUACAACUUUUUUUUUUUUUUUUUUUUGAGACAGUCUCGCUCCGUGGCCCAGGCUGGAGUGCAGUGGUGUGAUCUCGGCUCACUGCAAGCUCCGCCUCCUGGGUUUAAGUGAUUCUCCUGCCUCAGCCUCCCGAGUAGCUGGGAUUACAAGUGCCUGCCACCACACCCAGCUAUUUUUUGUAUUUUUAGUAGAGAUGGGGUUUCACUAUGUUGGCCAGGCUGGUCUCGAACUCCUGACCUCAGGUGAUCUGCCCACCUCGGCCUCCCAAAGUGCUGGGAUCACAGGUGUGAGCCACCACACCCAGCCACACCGUUAUUUUGAAAAACAGGCAGUAGUAACAGGUAUGGGGUUUCUUUUUGGGGUGAUAAAAAGUUAUUGAACUAGAUAGAGGUAAGGGUUGCACAACAUCAUGAAUGUAACUAAUGCUGCUGAAUUGUAUACAGUCCUGUGUGGCAUAAUGACACUUUGGUCAAUGUUGGACCACAUAUAUGAUGGUCUCAUAAGAUUAUAAUGGAGCUGAAAAACUCCUAUCACCUAAUGCCAUUGUAGUUGUCGUAAAGUCAAAGCACAACUCAUUACUGAUGUGUUUGUGGUGAUGCUGGUAUAAACAAACCUACUGCACUGCCAGUCAUAUAAAAAUACAGCAUAAACAAUUAUGUACAGUACAUAUACUUCAUAAUAAACGAUUAUGUUACUGGUUUAUGUA